AGACCUAGCGCCUCUGGGCUGUGCUCCUGUUGCUUCCCGCAAACCGCGGUCCUGGCGAGGCCUGGGCGUGGAGCGCGGCUGCCGCAGACUCCCUGGGAAGACAUGGAGUCAGGGUGCUUAGGGGUUUUUAGGCUCCUGCUCGCCUAGUGGCUGGCUUUCUCCCGGCUGAGAAGCGUCUCUGGGUUCCCAGAAAGGUAGGUUUCUCUGGCACCGAUUCGGGGCCUGCCCGGACUUCGCCGCACGCUGCAGAACCUCGCCCAGCGCCCACCAUGCCCCGGCAGCUCAGCGCGGCGGCCGCGCUCUUCGCGUCCCUGGCCGUAAUUUUGCACGAUGGCAGUCAAAUGAGAGCAAAAGCAUUUCCAGAAACCAGAGAUUAUUCUCAACCUACUGCAGCAGCAACAGUACAGGACAUAAAAAAACCUGUCCAGCAACCAGCUAAGCAAGCACCUCACCAAACUUUAGCAGCAAGAUUCAUGGAUGGUCAUAUCACCUUUCAAACAGCGGCCACAGUAAAAAUUCCAACAACUACCCCAGCGACUACAAAAAACACUGCAACCACCAGCCCAAUUACCUACACCCUGGUCACAACCCAGGCCACACCCAACAACUCACACACAGCUCCUCCAGUUACUGAAGUUACAGUCGGCCCUAGCUUAGCCCCUUAUUCACUGCCACCCACCAUCACCCCACCAGCUCAUACAACUGGAACCAGUUCAUCAACCGUCAGCCACACAACUGGGAACACCACUCAACCCAGUAACCAGACCACCCUUCCAGCAACUUUAUCGAUAGCACUGCACAAAAGCACAACCGGUCAGAAGCCUGUUCAACCCACCCAUGCCCCAGGAACAACGGCAGCUGCCCACAAUACCACCCGCACAGCUGCACCUGCCUCCACGGUUCCUGGGCCCACCCUUGCACCUCAGCCAUCGUCAGUCAAGACUGGAAUUUAUCAGGUUCUAAACGGAAGCAGACUCUGUAUAAAAGCAGAGAUGGGGAUACAGCUGAUUGUUCAAGACAAGGAGUCGGUUUUUUCACCUCGGAGAUACUUCAACAUCGACCCCAACGCAACGCAAGCCUCUGGGAACUGUGGCACCCGAAAAUCCAACCUUCUGUUGAAUUUUCAGGGCGGAUUUGUGAAUCUCACAUUUACCAAGGAUGAAGAAUCAUAUUAUAUCAGUGAAGUGGGAGCCUAUUUGACCGUCUCAGAUCCAGAGACAAUUUACCAAGGAAUCAAACAUGCGGUGGUGAUGUUCCAGACAGCAGUCGGGCAUUCCUUCAAGUGCGUGAGUGAACAGAGCCUCCAGUUGUCAGCCCACCUGCAGGUGAAAACAACCGAUGUCCAACUUCAAGCCUUUGAUUUUGAAGAUGACCACUUUGGAAAUGCGGAUGAAUGCUUCAGUGACAGAAACAGGAGAGAAAUCCCUGUGGCCAUGGGCCUGAGUAUCACAGGACUGCUUGUCAUUUUGCUAACCGCAUGUCUGGUGGCCAGAAAGAGGCCCAGUAGAGGAUAUGAACGCAUGUAAAGCCCCACUUUCUUCAAAAUGUGCAAAGUUAAGGUCUUGGGAAUUCCAGCAUCAUAUUCAGCCUGAAGUGAAAGGAUUGACCUGUCUCGUUGCCUGUUGCACCCUCCUGAGCUGAUUAGGAAACCUAACUUUCCACCAAAGGGCUACCGCAGUGCUGGGAAACAGCACCUCCCCUACUUCCUCCUGUUGCUUUGGGGAGGCCAUGCCAGGUGUGCUUGAUGCCCUCUGCCAUACCUGAAUAUACCAGUGCUGGCUUCCGGAAUUAGGGGCAAUAGGCAGAGACAUGAGUGGGGUGCUUGUGAGAAGGGAGAAAGCGAAAACCCGGAGGGAGAAUUGUGGGGAAGACGUUUACAAAUUGACUGAUUUUUCUUAUACAUUUUCAAGAGUCCUGAUUUUCAGUUUUUAAAAACAUUACUUUAAAAAAACCAAUGCAUUUCAAAGUUGAUUACAAAAUGAUUUUAAACUCCUGGAUUUUACCCAAAUUUUGUUUACUUAAAUUAUAGAUGAUCUUAAUAUGCUAUUAUUUUAAAAAAACAUAUCCUACUCUAUUGUAAUGUAUUAUCAGUUUAAAAAAUUAGGAAACUGCCUAUUUCACUUUUUUAAUUUAAAGCACAUAUCAAAGAUCAUGGCAAAAAAGGAGGGGCUCAAUAAAUGUUAGCCCUUCAGUUGCUUCAAUUUCAUGUGUUGUCUGCCUUCUUAGCUACUUUUUUCCGGGUUUGUCGGCUUUUCUUUGAUGUUAUUUUAUUCUUGUAAAUGUGUCCAUUUGGACCAUUGCAGGACAGGAGGGAGACAGAGCAGGGAGACAAUAUGGAAUGGCAAGCAGGAAGAGGUAGACCUGCCUGGAGGAUCACUCACUUCCCUUUUACGCAAACAUUCACCAAAAGCAGUACAUUCCUGAUGGGGGACGGUUGAUAUCUGAGGGAAAAAUUCUAUUAAAAUAUGGCUUAGGAUGUUAUUCAUGGUUUCCUAUUACAUUGAUGGGGGUUUUUCAUUCAGAGAAAAAGGAGAGGUAUGUUCUUAAUUGAUUCUACUGACUGGAAGUUUUCUUGUUUUUCCAAAUUUUCCAGAGGUGCCAUUCAUUAUUUUUAACAUGACAUUUAUGAAAUUUGGCAACAACUCUAAAACUACUGCCUACUUAGGAAAUGUACUGACUCUCCCAGGAGGCAUUUUUGCUCUCCUUGUUUUCUUAGAAUUGGGGCUGUGGGGAGGGCACACCGCAGCUUCAAAAGAGCACUAAGAGCCCCUGAAGACAUCCAGAGUGUCAGAAAAUGUCUGUUUCCCUCUUAAAACAGAUGUUGAUGACAAUCUGAUAUGAGGACCCGGGAGUUCCCCAAAGAGACUCGGGCUUAACAGCAAGAGCUUGGCUUUGGAGAGCUGUGAUCUCCUUCCACCUCCUCCUUCAAACUGGCACCUGCUCCAGGCUCCCCUGUGUCCAGUGUUAAGGGCACUCGAAAGUUCUGUAGGGCAGAGGACAAGGUGUUUAUUCACCAGCCACUCACUCUUCUGCAGAAUGAUUAAUGUAAGAUUUACCUUCUAGCAUGUGGAAAUUUCUCCCCUAGCAGAUGAAACAAGAAGCAGAAUUUAAAAUCAAGUAUAGAGGGAUAUGACCACUUAAAUUUAAUUUUCCUCCCUACCUUCUUCAGUGAGUUCUUUUGGAUGAUGGCCACUGCUUGGACUCCUGCUAUCUAUUCCCCCGACCCCAGUACUGAUUAUUUUUAGAAUUAAUUUGAAUUAGCAUUCUGGUAACCACAAAAAGCAAAGGUUUCAUUGGAAUGGCCAGUAAAUAAACGCUUGGAUGUGUAAUUUACUCACAGUCCUGCCCACUUUCCAGGUGGAGAGCAGAGGGGGCAGUGGAGCUGGGCUCCUCACCUGCCUCCCCUCCUAACCACACACACAUUCACCCUAAGAAGCCUGUGAUGAGAGGGAAAAAAAUUCUGUGAACUCCUCCAUUACUAAACCUGGAGGAAAAAAAAAAGAGUGGGUUGCUUUAUUUUCUUCGUUUUCCAACCUAGGGUAGUGAAAAUGGCUCCCAGGAAGACUGGGAAGAGUAAAGGGAGGGACAGACGGAGGUGAACUGGGGAAGAAACCCCAAAGCAGACGAUCGCUCCAGGCUGCAGCUAGUUUCCAUGCUACAAAAAAGAGAAUAGAAUCCAAAUAUCUAACCCAAAGGGAAACAUUAACUGAUCUCAGAUGCAAUGGAAAGAAAGACCAUAAUUCACCCAAACGGCAUCAUAGGAAAUGGAGUAUCUCGACUGCCACGCUCAAGCAUGAGCAAGAUGAAAACAAACUGCAUGGCCACUGUGCCAAAAUACUGCAGCAAAAUAAGAAUAGUUUGAAAUUAAAUUAAGAAAAGGAGUGAGGCCAGGCACGGUGGCUCACGCCUGUAAUCCCAGCACUUUGGGAGGCCGAGGCGGGCGGAUCAUGAGGUCAGGAGAUCGAGACCAUCCUAGCUAACAUAGUGAAACCCCGUUUCUACUAAAAACACAAAAAAUUAGCCAGGCGUGGUGGCAGGCGCAUGUAGUCCCAGCUACUCGGGAGGCUGAGGCAGGAGAAUGGCGUCAACCCGGGAGGCAGAGCUUGCAGUGAGCCAAGAUGGCACCACUGUACUCCAGCCUGGGUGACAGAGCGAAACUCCGUCUCAAAAAAAAAAAAAAAAAAAAAAGGAGUGAGGGUGUAUUAGUUUGCUAAGACUGUCUUAGUAACAUACCACAGUCUGGAUGCCUUAAAUAACAGAAAUGUAUAUUCUCACAGUUCUGGAGGCUAGAAAUUCAAGGUCAAGGUCUCAGCAGCAUUGGUUUUUCUGAAACUUCUCUCCUUGGCUGUAGAUGGCCUGUGUCUUCACGUGGUCUUCCCUCUGUACCUGUCUGUAUCCAUAUGUCCUCUUUGUGUAAGGAUACCAUUCAUAUUGGAUAGAGGCCCACCCUAAUGACCUCAUUUUAACUUACUGACUUCUUGAAAGACCCUGUGUCCUAAUACAUGUUCUGUGGUCCUGGAAGUUAGGGCUUCACCAUGUAAAUUUGGGGGCAGGGAGGGGAUACAAUUUAGUCCAUAACAGAAAGUUAGAAAUGAAAAUAGUAAAAUACAAAGAAAACAUAAUUCAAGGAACAGAAAGAAAUUCCUGACAAUUGCUUGAUGCUGAGAAUCACUUAAUGUGAAUUCCAGGUAAUCAGAGUUUAAAGAUAAGAUGUUAAAAUGAAAGAGUAAGAAAACAAGAUGAGUGUCAAAGCAAUACACUGCAUAAUGUAUAGAAACAGUCAGAGGCAGAAUAAAUAGGGAGGAAAUUAUAUUAUUUUCAUAGAGAGAAUGACUGAGAUCAUUACAGGUAAUACAGAUAAACCUUAUGAUUAAAGCAUUACAGGGAAGCUACUAGAUAUAGAAGCUAUUCAGCCCAUCCAACAUAAGUAUAAUUGGUGCCUCUGACGUAUAGACCUCAAAAAUAGAAUGAAGAUAUAUUUGAAGAUUUAAGGAAAUUUCCUUGAGAUAAAUAAUUGAAGUUGGGAUUAAAAGAGCAUGUCCCAAAAAAGAAUUGAUACCAAAAGUUUUACACUGGGACAUAUUGGAAACAAGCUAUAAAACUUCAAACAUGAAGAAGUCUUUAGGCCUUUAUGGAAAAUAAAAUAAAAUCAGCUAUAAAAAGGGAAAGUUAAAGUUGACCUCCAAUUUCUUGACAACAUUUAAAGCCAGCAAAUAAUUUCUACAAUGAUCUAAGAAAAAGAAAGUGUGACCCAGUGUGACCCAAAAAUAUGAAGUAUAAAGACAAUAGGCAGAUAUUCUUUUGUUUGUUUGUUUGUUUUGAGACAGAGUCUUGCUCUGUCGCCAGGCAGAUAUUCUUAAACAUGAAAUAAUUCAAAGGAUGCAACACAAAUAAGCCCUUAUAAAAAAAUAUUUGUUGACAAUGAAAUUCACCAAGAGAGGAAAUGAGUCGCAAUAUAAACAAGGAAAUAAACAGCCUUCAGGAAUAGAAAAGUCACAGUAGGCCUGGCCUAGUGGCUCACACCUAUCAUCCCAACUCUUUGGGAGGCUGAGGCAGGAGGAUUGCUUGAGCCCAGGAGUUUAAGACCAGCCUGGGCAACAUGGCGAAACCCCAUCUCUACAAAAAAUACAAAAAUUAGCUGGGUGUGGUGGCACAUGACUGUAGUCCCAAACUACUUGGAAGGCUGAGAUGGGAGGAUGUUGAUCCAUUUAUAUAUAAAACAUACUAAACAAUUAUGGGCCUGGGAACACAAACACACCUUCACAUAUAUGAAAUGAUAUUUGUACGUGGUUAUUCAUUACAACAUUAUUUAUAAUAGCAAAAAAAUGAAAACAAGCCAAGGGUCCAUCAAUAGGGGCCAGAUUUUAAAACUGUGAUUCAUCCCACAAUGGAAUCCUAUACAGCUACAAGAAGAAUGAGGAUGCUAUGUAUGUUUAAGGAAAGAGUUCCAAAAUAUGUUAUAUCAAAAAAUCAUAGUGCAUAAUAGUAUAUUCAUUAUUGUUCUAGCUGCACAAAGAAACAUCAGAAAUAUAAACAAGAACUAAGGAAAGGAAUCAUCUAAUGGGGACAGGGAGAACUAAGAGGAAGGGGCAAGGGUGGAAGUGAAACUUCUCAAUGCACAGCAUCUUGUAUUAUUUUGACUUUUCAAAUCAUAUGACAGUGUUAAAUCGUCAGAACACUUUUUUUUUUUUUUUUGAGAUGGAGUGUCGCUCUGUCUCCCACGCUGGAGUGCAGUGGCGUGAUCUCGGCUCAUUGCAAGCUCCGCCUCCCAGGUUCAUGCCAUUCUCCUGCCUCAGCCUCCCAAGUAACUGGGACUACAGGCGCCUGCCACCACAACUGGUUAUUUUUUUAUUUUAUUUUAUUUUUCAUAUUUUUAGUAGAGACGGGGUUUCACUGUGUUAGCCAGAAUGGUCUCGAUCUCCUGACCUUGAGAUCCACCUGCCUCAGCCUCCCAAAGUGCUGGGAUUACAGGCGUGAGCCACCGUGCCCAGCCAGUCAGAACACAUUUUAAAGACUACAGGAAUGAUAGUUAUCAAAUAGAAUUGAAGUGUCAUAAACCUGGACAAUGGAUCAAGGUCAAAGAUUGUUUCCUUAAGUUGAAAUAGCAACCAAAACGUUGUUCACACAGGGCUUGGGGGGCGGCUGCUGGCACUGUGGGCUUCUUAAUGAAAAAAUUUAAGCUAAAAACAUCAAAAAUUAAAAGUUUUUAAAACAUUUUUCAUUUAACAGGCCAUUGAAAUGCAUGGUACAAAAAUCAGUGAUAAGGUUAUUAUAAAAUGAAAUGGACAGAAUAAAUGUUUGAUUUAAUUUUCCAUCUAUGAGAAUUUCACAAUAAAAUCAGUUUACUUUUUAAAAAAGAAAAAAAAAACAUAGACAAUGUUAAAAACAGUGACAUAACUAUUCAAAAUUUGGAGUUGUCUGGGCACAGUGUCUCACACCUGAAACUUUGGGAGGCCGAGGUUGGAGGAUCACUUGAGGCCAGGAGUUCAAGACCAGCCUGAGCAACAUAGUAAGGACCCCAUCUCUUCAAAAAAGUUAAAAAGUAGCUGAGUGGGGUGGCAUUUGCCUGUACUACUAGCUACUUGAGAAGCUGAGGUGGGAGGAUGGCUGACCUCAGGAGCUGGAGGCUUCAGUGAGCUAUGAUCGCACCACUGCCCCCCAGCCUGGGCAACAGAGCAAGACCCUGUCUCAAAAAAAAAAUUGGGGGAGUUGAAGAGAGGGGAGAUGGAAGGGACUCUGUUAGUGCUACUCUUUCAAAACAGUAUCAAUAGAUAAUGUUUAAACUGGAAACGAAGUUUAGUAAACACAAGUCCAAUUUAUUUCAUAACCUCUUAAUGUAUUUCAUAAUUGUUUAAUGCAUACUUCAUAAUCUCUUUUUAGAACUCUAAAGGGACCCUUUAUGAACCAAUAUUUCCCAUGACAAAGAAACAUUGGUUUGUGAUAAUUCCUUCAAGUUCUUUUAUCCUAUUAAACACAAGUAAAAUUGAAAUUAACAAAUGUAAUAAAAUAGUACUUGUAUGAUCCUAUCUUAAUAAAAGUAUUUCUAUUUAUUUUUCUAA